AUCCCGCGCGUUGCGGUCAAGAUGGCGCUGGUGGCUUCUGUGCGAGUCCCGGCGCGCGUUCUGCUCCGCGCGGGGGCCCGGCUCCCGGGCGCGGCCCUCGGGCGGACGGAGCGGGCGGCCGGCGGCGGAGACGGCGCGCGGCGCUUCGGGAGCCAGCGGGUGCUGGUGGAGCCGGACGCGGGCGCAGGGGUCGCUGUGAUGAAAUUCAAGAACCCCCCAGUGAACAGCCUGAGCCUGGAGUUUCUGACGGAGCUGGUCAUCAGCCUGGAGAAGCUGGAGAAUGACAAGAGCUUCCGCGGUGUCAUUCUGACCUCGGACCGCCCGGGUGUCUUCUCGGCCGGCCUGGACCUGACGGAGAUGUGUGGGAGGAGCCCCGCCCACUACGCUGGGUACUGGAAGGCCGUUCAGGAGCUGUGGCUGCGGUUGUACCAGUCCAACCUGGUGCUGGUCUCCGCCAUCAACGGAGCCUGCCCCGCUGGAGGCUGCCUGGUGGCCCUGACCUGUGACUACCGCAUCCUGGCGGACAACCCCAGGUACUGCAUAGGACUCAAUGAGACCCAGCUGGGCAUCAUCGCCCCUUUCUGGUUGAAAGACACCCUGGAGAACACCAUCGGGCACCGGGCGGCGGAGCGUGCCCUGCAGCUGGGGCUGCUCUUCCCGCCGGCGGAGGCCCUGCAGGUGGGCAUAGUGGACCAGGUGGUCCCGGAGGAGCAGGUGCAGAGCACUGCGCUGUCAGCGAUAGCCCAGUGGAUGGCCAUUCCAGACCAUGCUCGACAGCUGACCAAGGCCAUGAUGCGAAAGGCCACGGCCAGCCGCCUGGUCACGCAGCGCGAUGCGGACGUGCAGAACUUCGUCAGCUUCAUCUCCAAAGACUCCAUCCAGAAGUCCCUGCAGAUGUACUUAGAGAGGCUCAAAGAAGAAAAAGGCUAACGAUUGGGCUGCCACAGGCUUACGGCCACACGUGCCCCUGUGGGUCCCAGGGAGGUCUUAAACAAGGUAUUUUUCAACUUAAAAGUACUGCCAGCGUUUCAUUUUGCUGAUGUUACGUAGAAGUUCCUGUUCCUCAUAGCCCAGUGGCCCAAGGCCCAGCCACACACAAACACACAUGGGUGCCUGUGCCCGUCAGGCAAGGGGAGUUGGAGGGCAGCCUUUUGACUUGGGAUUGUGACUGGCAGGGGAUGCCAUUCUGGACCUGGUGAGGUUGCCACGGAGUGUCUCUGUUCCCAAGGCAGAAUCGUAAGUCAAGUCCCUGGUCAUCCAUUCUGGCCUUUGGACUGCCUGCUCUUAGGUGUAAGGCCAGGUGGUCUUGGCCCCCAUGACCCACACAGAACUCCCCAGGGAAAAGCCCUUUGGUCACUGCCCUUACUCAUCAGGAUGAAGAGCGCACAGUGAAUCAGAGCAACUGGGGGAUCCUGAGCCAGCGGGAGUGGGACUCUGGAGGCAGCUGUGCUGCCAGGGAUCCAAAUGUCCCUUAAGAAGGAUUUUGCAAGAACCAAACUCAUCCAAA